AGCCUUUGCCAAGAACUCUAUACCCCAGGCAGGCCCACGGUGUCUCAUUGAUGAGCUCAGUGGGACCAAGGUGUGAGUGUUUCACAGGACAGAAGUUAAAUAUGGAAUACAUUUCCUGCCUGGACUCUCAGCUGAAACACCUCUCCAGUAUCUGCUGAUGUCUUUAAUGCCAGGCCUGGUGCCAGAGCAUCCCCGGGCGCUCGGAGGAAAGGGACACGCCUCGCUCCACAGCUCUGGAAUGGGGCAUUGGUCCUGGGGUCAGGAUUUUCCUCCUGUUCUAUGUGAAAAGCCUCUUCCCCUGUUAGUCAUCAUUUCCCCACUGUGGCUGAGCCCUGUCCCUUGGUCUUGGCAAGUCUAAGCUCCUGUGGAGGCUGAGAUUCCUGCAGGUGUCCUGACCCAGAAAUGAACAUCCAGCUUCUUUUAGAAGGCAGUGUUCUAGAAAUGUGGAGGCCACCUUCCCAUCUGUACGCAUGCACACACCCACACUCAUGGGGGCACACACACAUACACAUGCACACAUACACUCACAUGGACACAGAUAGAUGCAUGCACACCGACAUGUAGAUACAUGCACACACACAGACACACAUGCAUGCACACACGUGCUCACAGGGACAGGCACAGUCACAUGCAGGCACACGCAGACACAUGGACACACAUAUAGAUUCAUGCACACACACACAAGAUACAUGCAUGCACACACAGACAUGUGGACACAGAUACAGACACAUGUGCACACAGACACAUGGACACAGACACAUAGAUACAUGCACACACAGACACAUGCACACAGACACAUACGUGCAUGGACACACAGACACAUGGACACAUAGACACAGAUACAUGCACACACACGUACACAUGCAUGCACACACAUGCUCACAGGGACAGGCACAGACACAGGCACACACCACAGUCACAUGACCACACACAGACACAUACAUGAAUGCACACACACAUGCUUAAACAGACAUACAUUCACCACACACACUUAUAUGGACACAGAAAUGCACACACAGGCACACUUAUAACCUGAACAGUAACCUCCCACCUCUGUGAAUGUCACUGCGGCAUGGAGGGAGGAGGGAGUUGCCACUGGGGAGCCAGGGGCCUCCAGCCAAAGGACAGUGUGCGGUUCAGGGACAGACUCGAGCAGCAAGUCAAGAACCAGAAGUUCUGAUCACAGCCACUGGAGUGCGUUAAGAAGCCCUGUGGGCUGUUUUGUGUCAUCACCAAGCAGGCCUGGCCGCUGGUGCUGCAGUGCAUAGGAGCCCCAGAUUCAUCUGGUGAGGGUGAGGGUGCCAUCUGUGUGUGGCCCCCGAGCUGAAUCCACCACAUCUGCUCCCACAAAUAACAGAAGAGAGAGGCAGGGGAGUAUGCAGCCAGGGACAGGGGCCAGAGAGGCACCCUCCAGGAUACCUUUGGGGCCCUGCACCCUUUCCUGUUCCAUCCACAUGCUGUGGGCAGUGACAGGGGCAGGGCAGAAGGCCCAGCGGAGUGCCUCUGCGGGUCUGGUUUGUCAUGGAGGGAUCAGUGUGUUUCCAUGCCUGAAUGAGGAACACGCAGAUCACAGUUCCCAGAGUACUUUAUGUAAAGCUCGUCUUUGCGGCUUCUUGAUUUUUAUUUAUAGAGAGCUAUUUCACCUAAAAUAGCAGUUAUGCCUUGCCUAUGAGCCCAUGAGGAUGGGAUUUGCUCUUGGCAGUUUGGAAAUGAGGAGAGGCCUAGAGGAGGGGAAACCAAGUCACAGUCCUCAUGGGAAAGGUGGUUUGGGGCUGGAGUGGGCAGUGGAAGGGGCUAGGCAUAAAGAAGGUUGUAUCUGGGGCUCUGCUGCCAAUGUGCCCGGGCUUGGACCCUGGCUCGCCCCUAGCCCUUGGGAGAUCAUUCAACCUCUCUGUGCCUCGGUUUCCUUAUGAAUGAAGCGAGCACGCCAGUUACCCCUCCAUGGUGUCGUCGGGGCAAUUACCUGGAUGAGAGAUGUGCAGUGCUCAGCAGGAUUGUCACGAAGCAGGGGCCGGCAUGACAGCUGUGGCUAGGACUCCUUAUGUGGGGCCUCAGCCAAGGCUAGCACCAGGGAAUGGGCUGAUCGGGGCCCUUCAUAUGGCAGGUGAAGCUCUGCUAGGAACCUGGAAGCGCCAGGCUCCAGGGCAGCACAGAGGAGGGCAGGCAGAUGUCAAUCAGCAAGCCAAGCCCCACAGUCUGGAAAUUUGCACCAGUGUGAGUGGAGGUGGAGCCAGGGAGGAAGUAAAUCCCAGAGGAGAAGGCCUGGGCCAACAUUUUAGAGCCCAGCGGCAGUACUGAGCCCACUUAGGGAGGUGCCAUGGAGUCGUGGCCCCUGGAGCUCCUCGUGCGUCUGGUUGCUGUGGCAGGUAAGGGUCGGCCUUUGAGGUCCAGGGUCAGGAAAGGACAGGCGCCAUGGCGUGCAAUAACCCUUAUGGGAUUGAUAGUAAAACAUACAGAAAAUAUGUUUCAAUAGCAAGCACCACUGCCUCAGUCCUUAAGAUGCUAACCAGUUGGCUCCAAUGAGUGUGAGGUCAGCCGCGAUCCAUUUUGGGAAUUCUUUGAAGGCACAAGUGGUGACUCGUGGAAUACUUAAUAAAACAAAGUAAGGGUUGCCCCUGGAGAACAGAGGUCUGUACAGGCUGGGAGAGCAGCCAGGAGAGGACAGGAUGCUCAAGUCUUUUUGCAGGGCCAGUCAUGUCCGAACAACGCCAAUUCACUUGCCGUAGGUUGACAGGUGCAGAAGAUGAAAGAGUGGCGAGCCUCAGAUGCUAUUGCCUUGAUGUUAUUAGCUCCUGAUUCUGACAGCGCAGGGCCUGGCCCAGGGCACAGCUGCGCACAGGGUGAGCAGCAUGCCCUGCUGCAGGAGGGAUUUGCCUUGUCACCAUCCCCAUAGCAGACCCAGGACAAGGUCCGUCACGUUCCUGAUGCCAGGGGAUGUGACAUGUACCUCCCUCAGUGGCUUCCAGGUGCAGACCCAACACUGACACUGACCUUACAGUCAAAUGGCAAAGUAGAAAAUCCAACUGUAACACCAGCAAAGGACACUAGCUUGACAGCACUUUGGAGUAUCUGGAGGAAAUUAAAAGUAUGGUUAUGCUUGAAGACAUUUCACUAAGUCAUAAGUCUCUGGGCUCCUGGGCACAUCAAGAUUUGUGUCAUGCACUUUCUGGGAAGAAAACAAAAUGGAAAAUGAGGACCUUCCAUCAGGAAGCUGAUCGUUUCCUUCAAUGCAAGUACUCUUUGGAAACAAAAGCAAAACAAAACAAAAACCAUAAAAAAUACAAGAACAAGAAAUGCUGAAGACAGGUGGAAAGAAUGAAAAUAGGACUGAAGCAGGCCUGUGCCCUAGGCAGAGCCAGGCACACGCCUGCUGAGAGGACCCCACUAACAGGUGACCCAGGCAAGAGGCCCCCGGCCGGCUCCGUGUGAACAGAUCCUCCCAUCUUGUCGCGUCCGUGUCCACAGUGAAACUCCAGGCACCGCAGGGACGCUGGGGAGAGCCUUCUCUCCACACCCCCUUGGAAUGUGCCCCCCACUUUUCGCUGUUCUGGUGGGCUUUUGGUUUCUUGUCAGGGUUGGGGCUCUGCCAAGUAGCCACAGUGAACACAGAAAGCAGCCCUUGAGCCUGGCCUUCAGCGAGAGUUGCUAAGGGGUGGCUAGGAGAUGAGGAGGGUAGGCUCGGCCCCGCCGCCUCUGCUGUCUGGUUCGAGAUCAGCUGCUGGCCACCACAGGGGACAUGUGCAUUGUCAUCUAUCUUGGGAAAGACUUUGGUAAACAUCCAAGUUUCAAAGGAAAAACAAAACCUCACGGUGGCUCCCCUGCAGGAUAAAGGACAGCACUGCCUUCUCUUUUCUUCAGAGGCUGGCUUGAGCCAGGUUUGCAUAAUCCCCCACCUAGCCCUGAGGUGGGGAGAGAGUGUAAGAAGAGCAGCUUCAGGUGGGGUCCUUAGAUCCUUAGUGCAGUCCCCACAACCGCCCCCUCCACCCCUCCUUCCCCCGCUACAUUGCUGGAGUGUGAGGGGCCUAUAAGGCCAAAGGGCUGCCCAGGGGAGGGGCCCAGCACCCAGCUUACCACCUGCACGCCCAUCCCCCUUUCUCCAUCUUCCUUCCCCUUUGCCUUGCCUCUCCCUGCAUCCAGCCAAAGUCCAACUCUGCCCUUCAACCUGAAAGCCAAAUCCUCUAAGCAAAAGAACUGACACAUUUUGGAAAGUGGCAGGAAUUCAAGGUGCUGAUGCACGUGAUGCUGGGCAUGGCUUUGUGUGAGAUUGAAGCAUUGGUGGUGAUGAUCCUGUUGUGCUAAUUUCACUAAUGACUGGAGAAGAGAAAAUCUACAAGGCUUCAGGCAGGAGAAAUGGCUUCCCUGAGGCAAGUGUAACCUACAUUCCCAGCCCACCAGCCUGACGCCCAGCCAGGGAGAGAGUACCAUGGAUGGCAUCAUUGAACAGAAGAGCAUGCUGGUGCACAGUAAAAUCAGUGAUGCUGGCAAGAGGAAUGGUUUAAUUAACACCAGAAACUUGAUGGCCGAGAGCAGAGAUGGUCUGGUGUCUGUUUACCCAGCGCCCCAGUACCAGAGCCACCGGGUGGGGGCCAGCACAGUGCCGGCCAGCCUGGACAGCAGCAGGAGUGAGCCGAUGCAGCAGCUGCUGGACCCCAACACCCUGCAGCAGUCAGUGGAGUCCCGCUACCGGCCCAACAUCAUCCUCUAUUCAGAGGGCGUGCUGCGCUCCUGGGGGGACGGUGUGGCCGCCGACUGCUGCGAGACCACCUUCAUCGAGGACCGGUCGCCCACCAAAGACAGCCUCGAGUACCCGGAUGGGAAGUUCAUUGACCUCUCAGCUGAUGACAUAAAAAUCCACACCCUGUCCUACGAUGUGGAGGAGGAGGAGGAGUUCCAGGAGCUGGAGAGCGACUACUCAAGCGACACAGAGAGUGAGGACAAUUUCCUCAUGAUGCCCCCGCGGGACCACCUGGGCCUCAGUGUCUUCUCCAUGCUCUGCUGCUUCUGGCCUCUGGGCAUCGCAGCCUUCUACUUGUCCCAUGAGACCAACAAAGCCGUGGCCAAGGGGGACUUGCACCAGGCCAGCACCAGCUCCCGGCGGGCCCUAUUCCUGGCAGUGCUGUCCAUCACCAUUGGGACUGGCGUCUAUGUGGGCGUGGCCGUGGCCCUCAUCGCCUACCUCUCCAAGAACAACCACCUGUGAGCUUCCUGCGAAUGGAGGGGGAGCACCCGGGGCCAGGUCUGUGUGGACGUGGAGGAAGCAGGCAUACCGCAUGAUGCUGUACAGUACAAAUGAUUGCCAAAUGAUGCCACGAAGCCCUGGGAUUUCCUACCCAUGGAUUUAUUUUGUUUUUAUCCUUUAAUUUCAUGUUCACAGCACUGUGUAGAGCACCAGACAGACGGGCACUGCUAAUCCUUCCAAAGGAAAGCUCCAAAGAUCCCAGCCCGCAAGGCUGUCUCUGGAUGGAUUCUGGUGGAUGAAUGGCAACGCGGCUCUCUGCAGCCUGCCAGUGCCCAGAGUGCCACCGCAUUAGCAAUAUACAAACAGUCCAAAAAAGUGUUUAUUUUUUAUGGAAUACGGUGCAAUAGGCAGAGGACAAGGGACACAUCACUCUUCUGUCUGUGGCCCUGCUGGAGUCCUUUGUGCCCCCCGGAGUCCACACGCCUUCCCUGCAAGACGAGAAUGGGGCUGGGAAGAAAGAGGCAACACCACGGCUGGCAGGAGCCCCGCUGCACUGCUCUGCAGACCCAUUGGCCUGACCCUGAGAAGCAGAGCCAGCAAAGCCCGGGACCUGCCCCUCUUUCUUUCCCUUCACACCACCCCAGCCUCAGGAUGUCAAGCCACCUCCGGAACGUGUCUACACUCCACAGCUACCCCGCAGCAAUACGCACUCUUGGGACCUCGCUGAUCUAGGAUGGGGAGGCAGGCCACCGCCCCUCCCAAGACUCCUCAAGAAAGAGCCCCGCGGUUGCUCCGGAAACUCGAGGCACUGCAGCUAUGGGCACUGCCUCAGCCUAAAGACACAGGGGCGCCUCCCAAUCACCGCGCUGGCGGAUGCUCACCCCGUCAUAAGCAGAAACUAGUGAUCCUGGAAAUGAGAUGGGCCUUACUCUGUCGACUAAAUGAAUAGCUAUUUUCUUGUCAUUUUUUAAAGUGCAACUCUUGCUUCAUGCUGCUUAAGUUACCAGAUGAAUGCUGAGAAAUAAGUAAUCACAGACAUUUUAAUACCAUUUCAUUGCUGUUUUACGAGUGUUCAUUACUUAACAAAAAAUUAUCUUUUAGCUUUUUCGCUUAAGACUUUUCUUUCUGAUGAA